GACAGAGCAAGACUCUGUCUCAAAAAAAAAAGGAAAAAAAAAAGUUUUAUGAAUAAGUAAUUUAAGUAGACCUAUAUUCAAUAAAGAAAUAGAAUCAAUAAUUAUUAGUAACCUUCCAAAACAGAAAGCCCCAGGCCCAGAUGGGUUGGCGAGUGAAUUCCAACAAAUAUUUAAGGAAGAAAUGAUAAAAAUUCUCAACAAUCUUUCAGAGAAUAGAAGCAGAGGGACUACUUGCUAACUAGCUCUAUGAGACCAACAUUACACUAAUACCAAAGCAAGACAAAUUAUAAGAGAAAACUACAGACCAAUAUCUUUUAUGAACACAGAUGCAAAAAUCCUCAACAAAAUAUUAGCAAAUCAAAUCCAACAAUGUUCAAAAAGAAUUACACAUCGUGACCAAGUAGGAUUUCUCCCAGGUAUGCAAGGUCAAUUCUACAUUUGAAAAUCAAUUAAAUCCAUUAAUGCAAUUCACCACAUCAGUAGGCUAAAGAAGAGAAAUCACAUGAUCCCUUCAAUAGAGGCCAAAAAAGCAUUUAAUACCCAUUCAUGAUUUAAAAAAAAAAAAAAAAAAAAGCCUUCCAGCAAACUAGGAAUAGAGGGGAACUUCCUCAACUUCAGAAAGAACAUCUACAAAAAACCUGCCACUAAUAUCAUACCUAAUGGUGAAAAACUUGAAGCAUUCCUACUAAGAUCAGGGAUAAGGCAAGGAUGUCUCCUCACUACUCCUUUUCAGCAUUGUACUGGAAGUCCUAGCUAAUGUGACAAAAAAAGAAAACAGAAGAAAAGAAAGAUACAGGGCCGGGCAUGGUAGAUCACGCCUGUAAUCUGAGCACUUUGGGAGGCCAAGGCAGGUGGAGUACUUGUGGCCAGGAGUUCGAGACCAGCCUGGCCAGUGUGGUGAAAUCUCGUCGCUACUAAAAAUAUACAAAUCAGCCAGGCAUGGUGGUGAGCACCUGUAGUCCUAGCUACUUGGGAGGCUGAGGCAGAAGAAUCACUUGAACCCAGGAAGCAGAGGUUGCAAUGAGCCGAGAUUGCACCACUGCGCCCCAGCCUGGGUGACAGAGUGAGACUCUGUCUCAAAAAAAGAAAAAGUAUGUGGAUUGGGAAGGAAGAAAUAAAAUUGUCUUUGUUCACUGAAGACAUGAUUUGUCUAUGUAGAAAAUCUCAAAGAAUCUAGAAAAAAACCUCUUGGAACUAACAAGCAAUUAUAGUGAGUUUGCAGAACACAAGGUUAACAUACAAAACUCAGUUGCUUUCCUAUAUACUAACAAUGAAAAAGUGGAAUUUGAAAUGAAACAUACAUUACCAUUUACAUUUACAUUAGCACUCCCAGAAAUUGAACAAAUAGGCGUAAAUAUAACAAAAUAUCUACAAAAUCUUUAUAUAGAAAACUGUGAUGACAGGUGUCAAAGAACUACAUAAAUGGAGAAACAUUUCAUGUUUGUGAAUAGGAAAACUCAAUGUCAUCAAGAUGUCAAUUCUUCCUGACUUAAUUGGUAGAUUCAAUGCAAUCCCAAUCGAAAUCCCAGCAAUUUGUUCUAUGAACAUCAACAAACUGAUUGUAAAGUUUAUAUGGAGGGACAAAAGAUUCAGAAUAGCUGUCUUAGUUCAUUUUGCAUUGCUGUAAGGGAAUACCUGAGGCUGAGUCAUUUAUAAAGAAAAGAGGUUUAUUUGGCUCAUAAUUCUGCAGGCUGAACAAGAAGCAUGGCACCAGCAUCUGCUUCUGGUGAGGACCUCAGGAAGCUUCCAACCAUGGCAGAGGUGAAUGGGGAGCAGGUAUGUCUCAUGGUGAGAGAAGGAGGAAGAGAAAAAAGAACAUUCAUAUUUUGCAGGAACUAUGAGUGAGAACUGGCUCAAUCCCUUGAGAAUGGCACCAUGACAUUUAUGAGGGAUCUGUCCCCAUGAUUCCACCAGGUCCUACCUCCAACAUUGGGGAUCAAAUUUUAACCUGACACUUGGAGGGGCCAAAUAUCCAAACUAUUAUUCUUUCCCUGGCCCCCCAAAUGUCAUAUCCUUCUCACAUUGCAAAAUAUAAUCAUCCCUUCCCAAUAAUUUCCAAAAGUCUUAACUCAUUCCACUAUCAAUUUAAAAAAUGCAAAAUCUCAUCUGAGACUGAAGGCUAAUUUCUUCCAGCUGUGAGCCUGUAAGAUGAAAAGCAAGUUAUUGAAUUCUAAGAUACAAUGAUUGUGCAGGCAUAGGGUAAACAUUCCCAUUCCAGAAGGAAAAAAAUGGCCAAAAGAAAGCGGUAAUAGGCCUCAUGCAAGUCCAGAACUCAGCAGGGCAGACAUUAAAUCUUAAAGCUCCAAAAUAAUCUCCCUUAACUCCAUGUCCUGCAUCCUGGGCAUACUGGUGCAAGGGGUGGGCUCCUAAGGCCUUGGGCAGCCCCACCCCUUGGCUUUACUGGGGCACAGCCCAUAUGGCUACUCCCACAGGUGGGAGUUGGGCCUUUGGCCUUUCCAGGCUGAAAAUACAACCUGCUGGUGGCUCUACCACCCUCAGCUCUGGAGGGCAGCAGCCUUGUUCUACUAAGGAGUAGCCCAGUAGGGACUCUAUGGGGGCUCCAACCCCACAUUUCCCCUUGGCACUGCCCUAGUAGAGUCUCUCUGUGGGGGCUCUGCCCCUGUGGCAGGCUUCUGCCUGGGCAUGCAGACUUUCUGAUACAUCUUCCGAAAUCUAGGUGGAAACUGCCAGAAUGUGCUCUUGCAUUCUGUGUGUCUACAGACUUAACACCACAUGGAAGCUGCCAGGGCCUCUGAUUGGCAGCCUGAGCCAUGCCUGGGGCCUUUUGAGCCCUGACUGGGGCCUGAACAGCCUGAAUUUGGAUUGGGCUCCUGAAACCAUUCUGUCCUUCUAGGCCUCUAGGCCUUUUUCCCAUUGUCUUGCUAAUUUCUUCUGCAAGUGGUUGCUCUUCAGCCCCUUUAAAUUUCUCUCCUAAAAAUGCUUGUUCCUUCCCUACCACAGGACUGGGUUGCAAAUUUUUCAGACUUUUACAGUCUGCUUUCCUUUUAAUUUUAAGUUCAAACCUUAGAUCAGCCCAUUGCUCCCACAUUUGAUUGUGGACUGUGAGAUUUAGAACAAAGCAAUGAUAUUUGCUUUUACUGCUCCUAUUCAGAUGUUGCUGGAAGCCUCAGCUGGUGCAAUUAGUUAAGAAAAGGAAAUAGGCCAGGCAUGGUGGCUCAUACCUAUAAUCCCAGCACUUUGGGAGGCCAAGGAGGGAAGAUUGCUUGGGCCCAGGAGUUCAAGACCAGCCUGAGCAAGAUAGGGAGAUACCAUUUCUACAAAAAAAGCAAAAUAGGAAAGGGGAAUAAAAGGCUUACAGAUUGGAAAAAAGAAAUGAAACUGUCCCUAUUUCCAGAUGACAUGAUUGUCUAUGCAGAAGAUCUCAAGGAAUAUACCCACCCCCAACAACAACAACAACAAAACCCUCCUAGGACCUAAUUGAGGGAGUUUAACAAGGUCACUGGAUAGAAAUUCAACACAAGCCUUGACCAGGAAUUUUUUCCUUCAGGAGUAUAGCCAACUUAGAAGGACUCUCCACUUCAAACAAACAAACAAACAAACAAACAGGAUUCUGACCGAAACUAAUUUGCCCUGCUAGUCAGGCUGGCAAGAAUUAACAGAAGUCUCCAAAGAGUAAAAUUAACCAAAAACUGUGAACAGAAACUAGAGUGGCAGGCAGCAUAUCCCAUUAUCAACACCAUAAGUGGGUGAUAAGCCUCGGGUCAGCAGUUUGCUGGUAUAGGUGAAUCUGACACUUCCAAUUUCUUAAAUCCAAAGCCCCAAAAGAAAAGUGUUCUGGUUUCUGAGCUUUCUUUGUUUUGCUCUAAAAUGUGAAUAACAUUCACCUCACAAUGUCUGAAAAUAGGGUUAAUUAGGAGGCCUGUUGGAGUUAUUUCCUAGUUUCACUCUGCAGAUGCCAAAUAUCGGGAUGCCUUAGUAAUCUGUGUUUCUCCUCCCUCUGGCAAUACAACUGUUAAAAUUAGAUAAUUUGUUAUCUGUGAAAGUUUAAUUGGAGCAAUAUGUGAUGGAAAUGCAAAUUACUUAAUUAGGAGUUAGGGAGAGUAUGAGAGAACAAUGAAAUGAGAAUAAAUUAACAAAUAUUAUUAGAUUAAAUUUAUUUAUUAAUCGUGUUGGAUCCAAGUACCUUAUAGCUACCAAGGAUACAGGAUACAAAAAGAGGUUAUUCUCAAAUGGGGGAGAAGAUAAUUAAGUAUCCUGCAAAAUGCCUCAUGAUAUGUGCUAUAGUAAUAUUAGUAUGUACAGUGUGCUAUGGAACCAUCAAAGAGGGGAGCAACUGACUCUCUCCAAAAUUUGAAGAGCAAUGCAGUUGGAUUCUACUUCCAAUCUGUGAAACUGCCUCACAGUUAAAGUACUCUCUGAGGGCCCGGUGAGAAAUCAGGCAGAUACCAGAGAGGAAUCUAUUCUUACAAGAUAGCUGCAUAGGGUGAUAUCUGUGACUUUGCGGCUUUUUUAACUGAUUGCAUUCCCCAGUCAUUUGCAACUUGGGUGGCAGAAAGCUGAGAUUUUAUGAACUUGAAAUGUCAGGGGACAGAGGUCAAGGCUGGCGGAGCAAGAAAUUACAGAGGAAUCCCUGCAAACAAGAAAAAUCAUACGAAGGGUGAACUGCAAAAUUUUAGUAUAAUGACUGCUCAGGUGGUUGGCUGACAGCCAAAUUAUGUAGGCACAACAGAGGACCCCCGCCCCUGCCUCAAGAGGCCAGGUUAAAACAACAGCAGCUGGAAACCAUAAGAACAAAGAUAUCAGUACCUAUAUUGUGCAAGGGAGACAAAGUUUGCAGUUCGAAUCUAGGCAGGUUAAGUAUUAAUAUCUACUAGAACAACAAAAACCCCACAACAAUUCUUAGAAGAACACAGUUAAACCCAGUGUCUAGGCAUGCAAAGAAACAGAAGUGUGACUCAUACUCAAGGAGGGGGAAAGGGCAGUCAAUAGAAACUGACUCUGAGUGAGCCUAGUUGUUGGAUUUAACAGAAACUUCAAAGCAAUUAUUGUAAAUGUGUUCAAUGAGUUAAACUAUGACAUCAAUGAGUGGGGUGGAAAAUCUCAACCAAGAAAUGGAAACUAUAAAAAUGGAAAUUUGAGAGUUGAAAAAUACAGUAACUGAAAUUUUUUAAAAAUCUAAAUAGCUUCAACAGUAGAUUAGAAAACAAAGCAGAUUGGCAAAAGAAGCCAUGAAGUUCAAGCUAGAUCAAUAGAAAUCACCCAGUUUCGAGAAACAGGGGAGAAAAAGAUGGAAUAAAGUUGAAAAGAGAUAUGUAGGGCAAUAUCAAACAAUCCAUAAUAGGUAUAAUUAGAGUCUUAGAAGGAGGGGCAGCAGUAAAUUAUAGAAAAUUUUUUGAAGAAAUAAUGACUGGAAUUUUCUCACAUUUUGUGGGAAAAAAUUAACUUACCCAAGUAGUACAGCAGACUGAAAGCAAGAUAAUUACAAAGAAAACCACUUAUUGACUGUCCAGAGAAAAAUGGUAUAUUGUACAUAGGGAACAACAGUGCAGUUAACACCUCACUUCUUAUCAGAAACCGUGGAGGUCAAAAGACAUUGGACCAACAUAUUCAAAUGAUGGAAAAAAGAAAGCUUUCAGCCAAGAAUUCUGCAUCUGGAAAAAUUAUCCUUCAAAAAUAAGGGGAAAAUAAAGACAUUUUUGGAUAAACAGAGAUGAGAGAAUUUUUCACUAGCAGACCUGCACUAUAAGACAUUUUGGCUGAAGGGAAAUGACACCUAAAUGGAUAUUUGGAUCUACACAAAGGAGUGAAGAGCACAUGAAAUUGUAAAUGUGUGUAAAACAAAAAUAAUGAUUUUUUGUUAUGUCUUAAUAUCUUUAAAAGACAAGUGACUGAAAAAGUAUAGUACUACUGUGCUGAUGUGUUUACAAUGUAUACAGAUAAUACACAGGACAACAAAAAUACAGGAUGAGGCACAGGACUUCAUUGACUUAACUAGAGAGACCAGACCAAGGACAAAAGAUCGCAGUGGACUGUAUGUGAUUGACCUGACAAGAGCUGAGGGAGAAAAUAGACCUAUUGCCACUCUUGACUUAACUUUAGAACCUGUCACUCCUUCCCAGAAGGAGCCAACCAGUCUUCAGACAUGUGCCAGCCUCUCUGGCAAAGCGGUGAUGGAAGGGCACGUGGACAGAAGCUCUCAGCCUACAGCACGGAGAAUCAUUAACAGUGAUCCUGUAGAUUUGGACCUAGUGGAAGAAAACACCUUUGUAGGUCCCCCACCCGCUACAUCCAUCAGUGGAGGCUCUGUUUAUCCAACAGAGCCUAAUUGUAGCUCAGCCACAUUCACAGGUAACCUCAGCUUCUUGGCAAGUCUACAGCUGUCUUCAGAUGUUAGCUCCCUCUCCCCAACAAGCAAUAAUAGUAGGAGCAGCAGCAGCAGCAGCAAUCAAAAAGCACCCUUGCCAUGCCCACAGCAAGAUGUAUCUCGCCCACCACAGGCCUUGCCGUGCCCCCUGCGACCUUUGCCAUGCCCACCGAGAGCCUCACCAUGUCCACCACGAGCCUCCUCAUGCCCACCACGAGCCUUGUCAUGCCCAUCACAAACCAUGCAGUGCCAACUACCAGCUCUAACUCACCCACCUCAAGAAGUGCCAUGCCCUCGGCAGAAUAUCCCAGGCCCACCUCAAGACUCUCUGGGCCUACCUCAAGAUGUGCCAGGGCUGCCUCAAAGCAUAUUACAUCCACAAGAUGUGGCAUACCUGCAAGACAUGCCACGGUCACCAGGAGAUGUGCCACAGUCACCAAGUGAUGUUUCACCGUCACCAGAUGCACCACAGUCACCAGGGGGCAUGCCACACUUACCGGGAGAUGUGUUACAUUCACCUGGAGACAUGCCACACUCAUCAGGGGACGUGACACACUCACCUAGAGACAUCCCUCACUUACCAGGAGACAGGCCUGACUUUACCCAGAAUGAUGUACAGAACCGUGACAUGCCUAUGGAUAUCUCAGCUCUGUCCUCUCCAAGCUGCUCUCCCAGCCCACAGUCUGAAACUCCCUUAGAGAAAGUUCCUUGGCUCUCUGUCAUGGAAACCCCAGCCAGAAAAGAAAUAUCACUGUCAGAGCCUGCCAAACCUGGGUCUGCCCACGUACAAUCACGAACACCACAAGGUGGGUUGUACAACAGACCAUGCCUGCAUAGACUGAAGUACUUCUUACGUCCUCCGGUUCAUCACCUCUUCUUUCAGACGCUAAUACCGGAUAAAGACACAAGAGAGAACAAGGGUCAAAAAUUAGAACCCAUCCCUCAUCGAAGACUAAGAAUGGUAACAAAUACCAUUGAAGAGAAUUUUCCUCUGGGGACUGUGCAGUUUUUGAUGGACUUUGUGUCACCCCAGCAUUACCCACCAAGAGAAAUCGUGGCUCACAUCAUCCAGAAAAUCUUGCUCAGUGGCUCUGAGACUGUGGAUGUCCUAAAGGAGGCCUACAUGCUUCUCAUGAAAAUUCAACAGCUACAUCCAGCCAAUGCCAAGACAGUGGAGUGGGACUGGAAACUGCUCACCUAUGUCAUGGAGGAAGAGGGACAAACUCUGCCUGGGCGAGUCCUUUUCCUGCGUUAUGUCGUUCAGACCCUAGAAGAUGACUUUCAGCAGACCCUGAGGAGGCAACGGCAGCACCUGCAGCAAUCCAUUGCAAACAUGGUGCUUUCCUGUGACAAGCAGCCCCACAAUGUCAGGGAUGUUAUCAAGUGGCUGGUCAAAGCAGUAACUGAAGAUGGAUUGACUCAGCCCCCAAAUGGAAAUCAAACGUCUUCAGGAACAGGAAUCUUGAAAGCCAGCAGUAGCCACCCUUCUUCCCAGCCCAACCUGACAAAGAACACCAAUCAGCUGAUUGUGUGCCAGCUUCAGAGGAUGCUCUCCAUAGCCGUAGAGGUGGACAGGACCCCCACCUGCAGCUCCAAUAAAAUUGCCGAGAUGAUGUUUGGGUUUGUGCUGGACAUUCCUGAGAGGAGCCAGAGAGAAAUGUUCUUUACUACCAUGGAAAGCCACCUUCUGCGCUGCAAAGUGUUAGAAAUCAUAUUCCUCCACAGCUGUGAGACACCCACCCGCCUGCCUCUGUCUCUGGCCCAGGCCCUCUACUUUCUGAAUAAUUCUACGUCACUGCUCAAGUGUCAGUCAGAUAAAAGCCAGUGGCAGACUUGGGACGAAUUGGUUGAGCAUCUGCAGUUUCUGCUGUCCAGUUAUCAACAUGUUUUAAGAGAACACUUAAGGAGUUCCGUGAUCGACCGAAAGGACUUAAUAAUCAAAAGGAUUAAGCCCAAACCCCAGCAAGGAGAUGACAUCACAGUGGUAGACGUAGAGAAGCAGAUUGAGGCCUUCCGCAGCCGCCUGAUCCAGAUGCUGGGGGAGCCUCUUGUCCCCCAACUCCAAGACAAAGUGCACUUGUUGAAGCUCCUGCUCUUCUAUGCUGCGGACUUGAACCCUGAUGCAGAGCCCUUUCAAAAGGGCUGGAGCGGCUCCUGAGGGCCUGCCAAGCACUGAAUGCCAAGAAUACCUCCUGAACUCUCUCUCCAACUGCUCAGAAGCUCUAAAAGCAUGAAAAGUGGUUAAAAUCUUACAGGACCAAACCUGCAUUAUUUAAUCAGUAGGUUGUAAUUUCUAACUCUAGUAAAUAUCUUUUUUUAAAUAAUCCUAUCCUAGCCUGUUCUCAAAUAUGGCUUAAAUAUACAAGGUAUAUAUAUUUUUUAAUAAAUUAUUUAUCUAUACUUUUUUGAAACAGGUUAAUACUCUGUGCAUCACAUGUUUAACAUUUUCAUUCAAGAUGUGGAAAAAAUCCCUCUGCUGAACCUAGUCUAUACACCAAUAUUAUGUCAUUCAAGGUACCGACAACCUGUUUCAGGAGAGAGACGUUCAUUUUUCCCUAAUGAAAUGCAAGCAUUCUGUUAGACCUAUUAUAUUGCCUGUUAAUUUGACUGUAAUGAAUAGGGGGUAGAAACAAAAGGAUCAAGUGUGUUAUAAAACAUUUGAUGUUAAAAGGAGACAAUAAAAAGGCAAUGGUUUUUCAAAA